GGGUGAUCCUCUUAUGCCUGUGGCCUUGGCCUCUGAGGACGGCAGUGAGUGCUGUUCCCUCAGUACGGUGGAGGCUUCAAGGGCCUCCUAGCUGCUGUGCCUCUGCUGACAUUUGGCAGGCAGCUUCUGCCAGCCAAGGGUCUCACCCCAGCCACCCGGCUCUGCACCCACUGUGCUGCCCACAGGAGUGGUCCUGCCCAUGGAAGGGCCAGUUCAGGUGGCCGGAGCUCCUGAGCUGCCCUAGGGGACUGCUGUGGGUCUGAGGUGGUGAUGUCCCCCACGGCUGCCUGCGCCUGAGCCCCCACGCAUCCACCCCUGGGGCCACUCUGCUGUUCAGGAGCACCCACCCGUGUCCUCGACCAUGAGCAGCCCCCCAGCUUACCCUGGCAUCAGGAUCUCAGGGUGCCGGGCCCUUGGAGCAGAAGGCAGCUUGCUUUUCUCCCCUGACCAUGCUCUGAGGAUGCCGUUCCCUGUCCGCACCUGUGUUCUGUGUCGUUUUCGGGCGUAACUGGCAUCUGUGGAGCGUUCCAUUUCCUGUGGAACUCCGGAGCGCGGUGGACAGACUGUGCCGCUGCAGGAAGCUACAAAGAGGCGGUCCUGCCGUUUGCGGAGCUUUCCCUCUUGCCCCCGGGGGCUCUGCCCUGCACAGACAGUGACUGUGGUUCUGAGUUGCUCCCCAUCAAUGCAGAGUCCCUGGACAGGCUCCUGCCACCUGUGGGCACUGGGCGCUCUCCCCGGAAGCGGACCACCAGCCAGUGCAAGUCAGAGCCUCCCCUGCUGCGUACAAGCAAGCGUACCAUCUACACCGCCGGGCGGCCGCCCUGGUACAAUGAACACGGCACGCAAUCCAAAGAGGCCUUCGCCAUCGGCUUGGGAGGCGGCAGUGCCUCUGGGAAGACCACUGUGGCCAGAAUGAUCAUCGAGGCCCUGGAUGUGCCCUGGGUGGUCUUGCUGUCCAUGGACUCCUUCUACAAGCUGCUCCACAGCCUCCCCCACCAGGUGCUGACUGAGCAGCAGCAGGAACAGGCCGCACACAACAACUUCAACUUCGACCACCCAGAUGCCUUUGACUUCGACCUCAUCAUUUCCACCCUCAAGAAGCUGAAGCAGGGGAAGAGUGUCAAGGUGCCCAUUUAUGACUUCACCACGCACAGCCGGAAGAAGGACUGGAAAACACUGUAUGGUGCAAACGUCAUCAUCUUUGAGGGCAUCAUGGCCUUUGCUGACAAGACACUGUUGGAGCUCCUGGACAUGAAGAUCUUUGUGGACACAGACUCCGACAUCCGCCUGGUACGGCGGCUGCGCCGGGACAUCAGUGAGCGCGGCCGGGACAUCGAGGGUGUCAUCAAGCAGUACAACAAGUUUGUCAAGCCCUCCUUCGACCAGUACAUCCAGCCCACCAUGCGCCUGGCAGACAUCGUGGUCCCCAGAGGGAGCGGCAACACGGUGGCCAUCGACCUGAUUGUGCAGCACGUGCACAGCCAGCUGGAGGAGCAGAGGAAGCUACGUUGGGAUAUGGCUGCGCUGGCCUCGGCACACCAGUGCCACCCGCUGCCCCGGACGCUGAGCGUCCUGAAGAGCACGCCGCAGGUACGGGGCAUGCACACCAUCAUCAGGGACAAGGAGACCAGUCGCGACGAGUUCAUCUUCUACUCCAAGAGACUGAUGCGGCUGCUCAUCGAGCACGCGCUCUCCUUCCUGCCCUUUCAGGACUGCGUCGUACAGACCCCGCAGGGGCAGGACUAUGCGGGCAAGUGCUAUGCGGGGAAGCAGAUCACCGGUGUGUCCAUUCUGCGCGCCGGUGAAACCAUGGAGCCCGCGCUGCGCGCUGUGUGCAAAGACGUGCGCAUCGGCACCAUCCUCAUCCAGACCAACCAGCUUACCGGGGAGCCCGAGCUCCACUACCUGAGGCUGCCCAAGGACAUCAGCGAUGACCACGUGAUCCUCAUGGACUGCACCGUGUCCACGGGCGCGGCGGCCAUGAUGGCAGUGCGCGUGCUCCUGGACCACGACGUGCCUGAGGACAAGAUCUUUUUGCUGUCGCUGCUCAUGGCAGAGAUGGGCGUGCACUCAGUGGCCUAUGCAUUUCCGCGAGUGAGAAUCAUCACCACGGCGGUGGACAAGCGGGUCAAUGACCUUUUCCGCAUCAUCCCAGGCAUUGGGAACUUUGGCGACCGCUACUUUGGGACAGACGCGGUCCCCGAUGGCAGUGACGAGGAGGAAGUGGCCUACACGGGUUAGCUGCCCAGUGAGCCAUCCCGUCCCCACCACCCUCCUCCUGCCUCCUGACCCAGGACUGCUGAAUACAAAGAUGUUAAUUUUUAAAAUGUUACUAGUAUAAUUUAUUCUAUGCAUUUUAUAAAAUAAAUAAAGCUUUAGAAAAAUGAA